AAGCAGCGCUGUCGCCGCCGCCGCUGCAGCCGGAGUUGGAGGAGGGAGAAGCUAGGAAGAAAAUGGCGGCCGUGGCUGCAGAGGCGGCAGCGACUGCAGCGUCCCCCGGGGAGGGGGGCGCCGGCGAGGCCGAGCCGGAGAUGGAGCCCAUCCCCGGCAGUGAGGCCGGCACUGACCCCCUCCCGGUCACGGCCACUGAAGCGUCUGUGCCGGAUGGCGAGACUGACGGGCAGCAAUCCGCUCCUCAGGCCGACGAGCCGCCGCUCCCGCCGCCACCGCCGCCGCCGGGGGAGCUCGCCCGCAGCCCAGAGGCGGUGGGGCCGGAGCUGGAGGCUGAGGAGAAACUGUCCGUUCGGGUGGCGGAGUCGGCGGCAGCCGCGCCUCAGGGAGGGCCGGAACUUCCACCUUCUCCUGCAUCGCCGCCGGAGCAGCCCCCGGCUCCCGAGGAGCGCGAGGAGCCGCCGCUGCCUCAGCCCGUAGCCCCGGCGCUCGUGCCGCCGGCGGGCGGGGACUCCACGGUGUCGCAACUGAUCCCGGGCUCGGAGGUGCGGGUCACGCUGGACCACAUCAUUGAGGACGCGCUUGUCGUGUCGUUCCGCUUCGGGGAGAAGCUCUUCUCCGGGGUCCUCAUGGAUCUGUCCAAAAGAUAUGAAGUGCAGAGACUCCCAUUCACGGCUUUCCAUUCUGUUUCCUGCAACAGCACACGCUCUGAUCGUAUCUCACCUGUUUGCAAUGGCUUAUUAGUAUGUUUUACUCUUAAACUUGCUUGCUCUCCCAUCAAGACCCAGGAAUCCUUCUUUCCCAUUUGGGGAAAAAAGCCAUUUAAAAUUUCAUAUUGAAGUAUGGUGUUUGAGGGGAAAGAUGAGAGCAGUUAUUCUGUAUUAUUUAAUCUCAAAUAUCUUUUUUUUUUUUUUUGAGACGGAGUCUCACUCUGUCACCCAGGCUGGAGUGCAGUGGCGCCAUAUCGUCUCACUGCAACCUCCGCCUCCUGGGUUCAAGCGAUUCUCCCGCCUCAGCCUCCCAAGUAGCUGGGACUACAGGCGUGCGCCACCAUGCUGGUCUAAUUUUUGUAUUUUUUAACUAGAGCCGGGAUUUCACCAUGUUGGCCAGGCUGGUCUUGAAAUCCUGACCUCAGGUUAUCCACCCGCCUCAGCCUCCCAAAGGGCUGGGAUUACAGGCAUGAGCCGCCGUGCCCGGCCUCAAGUAUCUUUUUUAAAAAUAAUUUUGGAUUAGGGCAUUUGCACUUCUGUUUAUGUUUGUUUGUUUACUUAUUUAAUAGAGACAGGGUCUUGCUGUGCUGCCUAGGCUGGUCUCAGACUCCUGGGCUCAAGCGAUCCUACUGCCUUGGCCUUCCAAAGUGCUGAAAUUACAGGCGUGAGCCACUGUGCCCGGCCUGCACUCCUGUUUUCAUAAUUAGAAAGCAGAAUAAGGUGAGUGUGCUUUCUAUUGAUGUAUUUUAUUUAUUUAUUUAUUUAUUUAUUUUUGAGACAGAGUUUCGCUCUUGUUGUCCAGGCUGCAGUGGUACAAUCUCUGCUCACUGCACCCUCCACCUCCCUGGUUCAAGUGAUUCUCCUACCUCAGCCUCCCAAGUAGCUGGGAUUACAGGCAUGUGCCACCACGCCUGGCUAAUUUUGUAUUUUUAGUAGAGAUGGGGUUUCACCAUGUUGGUCAGGUUGGUCUCAAACUCCUGACCUCAGGUGAUCCACCCACCUUGGCCUCCCAAAGUGCUGAGAUUACAGGCAUGAGCCACCUCGCCCGGCCUCUACUGAUGUAUAUAAUAGUAAGAGACACUCUGGUGUGUAUGCUGUUGAAUGAAACAGAAGAGAUGGCCAGUGAUUGUGUGAGAAUCUGGAUUUCAAAUCUGCAAAAGGAAGGUGCAGAAGAGACCAUGAAACGUAUGGUGCAAUAGCCCUACUUUUGGUGGGAAAAAUAUACAGCCAUUCUGGUGAAGCAGUUUGGGCCCCAUGGUAUCCCUGUGACAGUAUUUCCCAAAAGGGAAUAUAAGGAUAAACCAGAAGCCAUGCCGCUCCAAAGUAAUACAUUCCAAGAAGGGACAGAAGUCAAGUGUGAAGCAAAUGGUGCUGUUCCCGAUGACCCUUCUCCUGUCCCGCAUCCCGAGCUGAGCUUGGCUGAAAGCCUGUGGACUUCCAAACCACCACCUCUCUUCCAUGAAGGAGCACCUUAUCCUCCCCCUUUGUUUAUCAGGGACACAUAUAACCAAUCAAUACCUCAGCCACCUCCUCGGAAAAUUAAGCGACCCAAACGAAAAAUGUACAGGGAAGAACCCACUUCAAUAAUGAAUGCUAUUAAACUACGACCCAGGCAAGUUCUGUGUGAUAAAUGUAAAAACAGUGUUGUUGCUGAAAAAAAGGAAAUUAGAAAAGGUAGUAGUGCAACUGACUCUUCUAAAUAUGAAGAUAAAAAACGGAGAAAUGAAAGUGUAACUACUGUGAACAAAAAACUGAAAACUGACCAUAAAGUGGAUGGGAAAAACCAAAAUGAAAGCCAGAAAAGAAAUGCUGUGGUUAAGGUUUCAAAUAUUGCUCACAGCAGAGGCAGAGUAGUAAAAGUUUCUGCUCAGGCAAAUACAUCAAAAGCUCAGUUAAGUACUAAAAAAGUUCUCCAGAGUAAGAACAUGGAUCAUGCGAAAGCUCGGGAAGUGUUAAAAAUUGCCAAAGAAAAGGCACAAAAGAAGCAAAAUGAAACCUCUACUUCCAAAAAUGCACAUUCAAAAGUCCAUUUCACACGUCGAUAUCAGAAUCCUAGCUCAGGUUCCCUUCCACCCCGGGUUCGUUUAAAACCACAGAGGUACAGGAAUGAAGAAAAUGACUCUUCUCUGAAGACAGGACUUGAGAAAAUGCGGAGUGGCAAGAUGGCACCCAAGCCCCAGUCUCGCUGCACCUCUACCCGCUCAGCAGGUGAGGCCCCUUCAGAAAAUCAGAGUCCCUCAAAAGGCCCUGAAGAGGCCAGCAGUGAGGUUCAGGACACAAAUGAAGUGCAUGUGCCUGGUGAUCAGGAUGAACCACAGACAUUGGGCAAAAAGGGCAGCAAAAACAAUAUCUCUGUUUAUAUGACCCUAAAUCAAAAGAAAUCUGACUCUUCCAGUGCUUCAGUGUGUAGCAUUGAUAGCACAGAUGAUUUGAAAUCUUCCAACUCUGAGUGUAGUUCUUCUGAAAGCUUUGAUUUUCCUCCAGGCAGUAUGCAUGCACCUUCCACCUCCUCCACUUCCUCCUCUUCAAAGGAAGAGAAAAAGCUCAGUAAUUCCUUGAAAAUGAAAGUCUUUUCCAAAAACGUCUCUAAAUGCGUCACACCAGAUGGCAGGACCAUAUGUGUAGGGGACAUUGUUUGGGCCAAGAUAUAUGGCUUCCCUUGGUGGCCAGCCCGUAUUCUUACUAUAACUGUGAGCCGGAAAGAUAACGGCCUUUUAGUCCGACAGGAGGCCCGUAUUUCAUGGUUUGGGUCUCCAACAACAUCUUUCCUUGCUCUUUCACAACUCUCCCCCUUUUUAGAAAACUUCCAGUCACGCUUUAAUAAGAAGAGAAAGGGCCUGUAUCGCAAGGCUAUCACAGAGGCAGCUAAGGCUGCCAAGCAGCUGACCCCCGAAGUGCGGGCUUUGUUGACACAGUUUGAAACGUGAACAUGGGCAGUAAGGUAGGCAAGACCAUUGGAAGUCACCACAGAUUUUCUAGUCUAGUUAGGAAUAAUUUCUACAAAAUAGCGUGGCCAGAUUGGAGAGAGAAGUUGCACUCAGUUGGCUGGCUUUUUAAUACUUACCUUAUAGCCAUUUUUAGACUGAGAGCUUAAACUGAACAUAUAAUCAAAUUUUGUGUUAAGGAAGUGAGAUUUUAGCAGUAUUUUUCAGUUUUGAAGUUCGAAACCAUCCCAAGGCAUAGGAGCCAUAGCCUCAACUGAAAUUGAAUUUUUGUAGGGACUGUUAAUUGCCAUUUGUACCUAAUACUGUAUAUAUACAUAUAUAUACGUGUGUGUGUGUGUAUAUAUAUAUAUCCGUGUAUGUAUAUAUACACACAUAUAUAUGUAUAUAUACACAUAUAUAUAUAUGAAAUACAGCCUGUCACUGUGUGACACAGAUUGCAUAUUUGGGAUUGCAAUAAGGGCUUGGUGAGCUGGGGGAAUAGUGGAUAUUUAAUGACUACUUGUUUUUUAAAUAAUGAACACUUAGCCUUUCUAUGCGCAUAAUGGUGUAAAAGUUAGAUGGUUAGGUGUUUGACAAACAGAUGGUUGCAAUUCAGUUACAGACUGGGGAAAUAGCCCAGUGUUUGGGAUUAAAACUGUCAAGACUGGAUAGGUGUUAGUCAUCACUGUCUUUCGUCCAGUGGGGAUUUAAUAAAUACUUUCAAGCUUCUGGUUUGGGAGUUUAGAUAGGUUUGAUUUUGGAUUUGUAAAUAGUGAUUGCUAAAUUUGGUCAGAUUUCUCCUGACUGGCUGUUCCUAAAUUCUUAGGAUAUGUCCCAGUAAAAUUAUACUUUGUGAAUUAAUUGUCAUAUGUGUAAUUGUUGCAUUUUGGAUGUACCUAAUUUGAUAAUUAAAACAAAAUAAUUUCCGUUUAAGGUAUCUGUUUGCAGGUCAGAAAAUGAGAAAAUGUAAUUGUGUAAUGCUCUGAAAUGUAAAAAAAAAAAAAAAAACCAAAAAAAAGCUGUAAAUAAAAUCAACUAAAUCCAAA